CAAACUUGAAGAUCUCACAGACCUAAUAGACACGGCCUUUCCUCUCUGCCUCUGGCUUUAUGUCUCUUUCAUCCUCCUCUGCCUUUCCCCUGCCCUUGAUCCCUUCUGCAGGUCUUGGCUGGUUUCAGGAAACGGGUCCCAUCCCAUGGACUCCCACUCUGGGGAGCCUGCGCUCCUGCCCUGUGGGACCUGUGACAUGGUUUUCCGCUCCUCAGCUCUGUUAGCCACCCAUACUCAGCGCUUCUGCAUUGGCCACCCGACCCAAGAGAUGACAUUUGGAGCACAGGCAUCAGUUGCCACUGAACCCCAGCGGGCCGCGGUUGUGCCACAAGAACACCAGGGCGUGCCACAAGAACCCCAGGGCCUCCCAGACCAGCAGGCCAGUAGAUCUGCUCUAAAGAGGUUAACAGAGGAGGUGCAGUGGCUGCGGCUAUCCCUACAGGAAAUGCGGCCCUGGAUAACAGAGGUCCCCAGGGUGUUCGCGGGGCCCUGGACACGUUCCGAGGCGCGGCCUCAGAGUCCCAUGUCCGAGGCGGUGGGAAGCCCCAGCGAGCGGCUGCGGGCGCUGUUCAGGACUCGCGCGAGGCGCGUGGCGGAGAUGGAAGCGCAGAGCCGGGCCCUGCAGCUACGCGGCGAGGGUGAAGGAGAUGGGGGACGGGGACCAAGGACCUCCUCUGCCCUCGCCGUUUGGCUUAAGCUUGCUCGGGCCGGUUCUGACUCGGCCCGCAUUCCCUCAGAACUGAGCCGACGCCUCCAAGUUGUGGCCUGUACGCGGGGCGGGAUGUCCCGCCUCUUCGGCCUGGAGCAGGAGAUUCGAGAACUACAAGCUGAGGCCGGGAGGACGCGGGGAGCUCUAGAGGUGUUGGGGGCCCGCAUUCAGGAGCUGCAGGCGGAGCCAGGGAACCCGCUGAGCUCCCGGCGAGAGGCAGAACUUUAUUCUCCAGUGCAAAAGGCCAACCCGGGAACUCUGGCUGCCGAAAUCCGGGCGCUGCGGGAGGCCUACAUUCGAGACGGGGGCCGGGACCCCGGCGUGCUGGGCCAGAUAUGGCAGUUGCAGGUGGAGGCGUCUGCACUGGAGCUGCAGCGGUCGCAGACCCGCAGAGGAAGGGCAGGUGCCACCUCAGGGGAGCUUCCAGUAGUGGAGGCUGAAAACCGGCGCUUGGAGGCAGAAAUCUUGGCCUUGCAAAUGCAGAGGGGUCGGGCACCCUUGGGGCCCCAGGAUCUGCGACUCCUGGGGGAUGCCAGCCUACAACCGAAGGGGAGGAGAGAUCCCCCACUCCUCCCGCCACCGGUGGCACCACCGCUGCCACCACUUCCAGGCUUCUCGGAGCCACAGCUUCCUGGAACAAUGACCAGAAACCUGGGCCUGGACUCACACUUCCUCCUGCCCACAUCGGACAUGCUGGGCCCUGCACCCUAUGAUCCUGGGGCUGGCCUGGUCAUUUUCUAUGAUUUCCUGCGGGGCCUUGAGGCUUCCUGGAUUUGGGUGCAACUAAGGACUGGCUUGGCACGCGAUGGACGGGAUACAGGAAGGACCACAGCGUUGCCCCCAGCCCUUUGCCUGCCCCCACCUCCUGCUCCCGGGCCCAUGGGCAACUGUGCCAUCCUUGCCAGCAGGCAGCCUGUGCCCAGACUACCACCCUCAUCAUCAGUAUCUUUGGUCUGUGAGCUGCAGGUCUGGCAGGGGCUAGCAUGGGCUAGGGCACCACAGCCAAAGGCUUGGGUCUCACUUGGACUAUUUGACCAAGAUCAGCGGGUGCUAAGUGGCCGCUGGCGCCUCCCACUUCGGGCCCUUCCUCUGGACCCCAGCCUUAGCCUUGGGCAGCUGAAUGGGAUUCCUCAGGUGAGUGUGGUGCGCAGGGAUUGGGCAUACAGCAAAGUACAAGUGCAAUACCAUUUCAUCUCUCCCCAGGCAGGUCAGGCUGAGCUCUUUCUGCGGCUGGUGAAUGCAAGAGAUGCAGCUGUACAGACACUGGCAGAGAUCAAUCCAGCAAGUGUCCAUGAGUACCAGUACCCACCUCCGGUGUCCAGCACAUCUUCACUGGAAGCCAGCUUCCUCACCCCCGCAGUUGGCUUUGCUGAUCCCCCACCUCGUACAGAAGAGCCCCUCAGUGGAGUCAAGGAUAGAGAUGAGGGUUUGGGCCCUCACCACAGUUCUGACUUGCCCCCAGUGAGUUUCUGAACCCAAGUGAAUGUGGAGAUGAGCAUCUGAACAUGCACAGGACUGGGGCCUAUUUCCAGACCUACAGGUUUACUACUCCAUGUUCUGACAUUGGGUCUAGAAGCAUCUAGCAGUUGAGUACAGAAAACCAGUUCCAACCACAGCUUUACCACCUCCCGUUAAGUCCUUAACUUUUCUGUACCUCUUCUGUUUUUGUAAAACAGAUUAAGGAUUAAAUGAGUUUGUCAGGUA